GAAAGGAGUGUUCUAUAGAGUCCAGUUGGCCAGCCAUACUGCUGGCCAGUUACCCAGGAGGGGAGGCACGCUGACCUUUUGAUUCCUGUUUGCACGGAGCAGGGAGUUAGCUGGUCAGAUGGUCCCCAGUGAGAACAAACACAGAGCUGAGGGUCCCAGAGGGAAAAGCUGGGGUCUGAGGCUUAGGGGCUAAACCCUGAAGCCACAGACGGCUCCAAUGCCAGCUUCCCUGGGUAUAGAGAGAGGGUGUUCGUGUUCUCUCGGGGGCCAGCAAAGGCAGGGUCUUUGAAAGGGGAAACGUGAACAGAUGAAGCUCCACCACCAUGGAGGUGUGGUCCUGGGUCUGUGUCUUCUUCCCCUUCCUGGAUUUGGGGGCAUGGAUCUGGUCCUUGCCCUGGCUCCCAGGCACAUGGGUGGCUGGAGCCAGGCAUCAUGGGGUGGGUUUGGUUUGGGGCGGUUCAGAAACAAGUGAGGACAGGUCUUCGCUGCAGACCCAUUUAGUCCUUGACAGUGGAUGUCGGUACUGGCUCGAAUGGAGACAGACUGGGGAGAAGAGAGGACCGGCCAGCUCUCUUGUAACCACUCUGCAGCGCCAGCUACUGAACAAAUGAGAUGAUGAUCACACAUGCUCCCGAGUCCCCUUUGUUCAUCAGGCUACCCUAGGUCAAACUGGCUUCCCGGUGUCUGACUCAGGAGGCUGCAGGAAGCGCACCCACACCGUGGCCAGCUUACUCAGGGGCUCGCGACAGUUGCUUUCCAGCUGGGGCCUUGCUGGGGACCAUCGAUGAUCUCGGCCUGAUGGACGCCUGGUGUGGACGAUGAGGGAAGAACGUGCCCCCCACACCCAAGAGGUGACCCCUGAGCCAGCCCCGGAUGACCCUGCGACCUGGAACAAUGCGGCUGGCCUGCAUGUUCUCUUCCAUCCUGCUGUUCGGAGCUGCAGGCCUCCUCCUCUUCAUCAGCCUGCAGGACCCUACGGAGCUCGCCCCCCAGCAGGUGCCAGGAAUAAAGUUCAACAUCAGGCCAAGGCAGCCCCACCACGACCUCCCACCAGGCGGCUCCCAGGAUGGUGACUUGAAGGAACCCACAGAGAGGGUCACUCGGGACUUAUCCAGUGGGGCCCCGAGGGGCCGCAACCUGCCAGCGCCUGACCAGCCUCAACCCCCGCUGCAGAGGGGAACCCGUCUGCGGCUCCGCCAGCGCCGUCGCCGUCUGCUCAUCAAGAAAAUGCCAGCUGCGGCGACCAUCCCGGCCAACAGCUCGGACGCGCCCUUCAUCCGGCCGGGACCCGGGACGCUGGAUGGCCGCUGGGUCAGCCUGCACCGGAGCCAGCAGGAGCGCAAGCGGGUGAUGCAGGAGGCCUGCGCCAAGUACCGGGCGAGCAGCAGCCGCCGGGCCGUCACGCCCCGCCACGUGUCCCGUAUCUUCGUGGAGGACCGCCACCGCGUGCUCUACUGCGAGGUGCCCAAGGCCGGCUGCUCCAAUUGGAAGCGGGUGCUCAUGGUGCUGGCCGGCCUGGCCUCGUCCACUGCCGACAUCCAGCACAACACCGUCCACUAUGGCAGCGCUCUCAAGCGCCUGGACACCUUCGACCGCCAGGGUAUCUUGCACCGUCUCAGCACCUACACCAAGAUGCUCUUUGUCCGCGAGCCCUUCGAGAGGCUGGUGUCCGCCUUCCGCGACAAGUUUGAGCACCCCAACAGCUACUAUCACCCGGUCUUCGGCAAGGCCAUCCUGGCCCGGUACCGCGCCAAUGCCUCUCGGGAGGCCCUGCGGACCGGCUCUGGGGUGCGUUUUCCCGAGUUCGUCCAGUACCUGCUGGACGUGCACCGGCCCGUGGGGAUGGACAUUCACUGGGACCAUGUCAGCCGGCUCUGCAGCCCCUGCCUCAUCGACUACGAUUUCGUAGGCAAGUUCGAGAGCAUGGAGGACGAUGCCAACUUCUUCCUGAGCCUCAUCCGCGCGCCGCGGAACCUGACCUUCCCCCGGUUCAAGGACCGGCACUCGCAGGAGGCGCGGACCACAGCGAGGAUCGCCCACCAGUACUUCGCCCAACUCUCGGCCCUGCAAAGGCAGCGCACCUACGACUUCUACUACAUGGAUUACCUGAUGUUCAACUAUUCCAAGCCCUUUGCAGAUCUGUACUGAGGGGCGCCGCAGCUGGCCGGGGCCGCCCUGCCCCGGUCACUCACCUGUGCUCCCGGGCAUCCUCCUGUCCCUGGCUCCUCAUCCUGGGAGCAACAGGGCUCUGAGGACGUGAGGAGCCAUCGCUGUGGGAGGCAGCAGGCCCCGGGUGGGGGGCAGAGGCGCCCAGCCUUGGAUGGGGACCCCAGCCCCUGGCCUGUACCUGUUUCCUCAUUCCUUGGCUGAGGGAGAGGCUGAGAACUGGGCAGACACCCCUGGAGCUCAGCCGACAGUUUUGAUGAGCAGGGAAGUCUGAGGCCCAGAGGACGGGGGGCCCAGCGGUAAGGGAUGUCCCGCACUCCCUUAGCCAUUGCCUUGGACCAAACCACGUGGUUUGCAGCUUUUCUACGAGCCAGGGGGGAGGUUCCCUUGGAUUAAGGUUCCAAAUAAAGCACAUGGUUUCCAGAGCA